ACUCGGCGGCCAGUGUGCGCAGGUCUCCUGGUCGCCGGCCAGAGGGCGAAAGCAUUCACCCGAGGCCCCCAGCUUCGCGGCUGCCUUGGCUGCGAGCAACGAGGGAAGAGGAGGCAGGCGCUCCAAAACUGGGCGAAGAUUCCUAUCCUAAUUUCUAACUCGAGCCUCCCACCGUCAGUGCGCUUAAUGGCGCUGCUGGCCGGAUGGAUAAUCGAGCUCUCUGGAGGGACAGACGCGGCCGCCAUCCCUAAUAAAUCGUGAAUAACGAAUGAGGGAAUCGACCAUCCUCAUGAGGCCCACGGGCGUCCAGUAACGCAGUAUCGAUUCGCUUCCCCGGCGUCGGCCUCACCGCUACUCCCGGCGUUUCCAAGCCUCCCUCCUCGUUCUCUCCCUCCUGCCGGAGCCACUGCGGACCGGAGCCCCAGCGCCAGGUGGAGCCGGGGCGCCAGUGGGAGUCGGGCCCAGCCGUCUUGGCGCUCGCCCGACUCUCCCGCCCGCGCGCCCAGGGAGGCGCACAGGCAGCGCGCAGCGCAGGGCGCGAGCGAAAAAUGCGGGAAUCAGCGCCAGGCAGGAGAAAAGGCGCGGGCCCACCUUACAGCCCGGCGCCUCGUUUCCUAGUCCAGUGUGGCCGCUCGCCUUCGGCCGGAUUAUUGUGUCCCAGACCCGGAGCCUGAGUUCCCAUCCUCAGCGGGCCUCCGUUCUUCUCUGCCCGAGCACGCCGGGGGCGCAGCCUCCGCCAGAGCUACCCGAUCCCCCCGCGGCGAGGCCCCCCACCCGGCCUCACCCCGCACCUCCACUCCCCUCUCGCGAUUGCUCCCUGCCAGGCGCCCAGGCUGGAUCCUGGUGCGCCGCUUUUCGGGGCCAGCGCCCCUGCCGCCGAGGGGGCAAGGGGAGUGGGGAGGACACGCUCGCCCUCCCAGAUGCAGUUAUUAAUUUUAAGGGAGUGUCACUUGGAGUGAAUGAAAAUCGCUCGGACGCCUGGCUGAAGGCGUCGCGUCCCCCGCCGGAGCCCCGCGCCCUUUGGUCUAGGCCGGGGCGUGGAGGACCACGAGCCACCUUUCAGCCCAGUCCCCAUUUCACCAUUUUCCAGGCGCCCCAGUUAGGGAUGGGCAUCACAGUGUCAGUGGGGGGAACCCAUAUUUUGAAGGGAGGGGGGCUAACUGCGGAAGGUAACAUAAGAGAAUCCAUCCUCCGGGGUCGGGGCGGCCGCAUGGGAAGGGAGGGGUCUCGUCCUGGCUAGGGACCCGGCAGCCGGUGGCGGGGAGCGGCCGCGCCAGCCUCCCCCUCCUCUUCCCGUCUCUGCCAGCAUCCUGAAGGAAUGAGGUCACGUGGGUUUCUCCCCUCCCGCCGCCCGGGCGAGCGACACGGCUGCGGCCCCCCUCCCCUCCCUUCCCUCCCUCCCUCCCAUCCCCCCCUCCCCGAGACCCACCGGACCCCGAACCCAGGUAAGCGGAGCGGACUCCCCCUGCCUUUCCCUCUCCUGGCCUGUAACCCUCUGGGGAUUGGGAUGGGGGCCGGCCGUUCUUCGCAAGCCCCGAUGGGAGGGGGAGGCUCUGAGCCGAUCCUGCCUUCGCACCCCCCGCGCCCCGUCAGUCCCUAGCCCAGCUUGCCCCGUCCGCCUUUCUUUCUCCCUUUUUUCUGUCCCUUUUUCCCUUUCCUCUCUUCCAAGAUGGCCGAAACGGGCUCCCCGUCUUAACGAUUUGGCGUCUCCCUCGACCACCACCUCUUUGUGCAGCAGCCCCCGGGCAGACCCUGUUCCGAGGGCAACGCUCCCCAGUCCCCCCACCCCCGACCCCGGAAUCAUGCAUCGGACUACACGGAUCAAAAUCACAGAGCUGAACCCCCACCUCAUGUGUGCCCUCUGCGGGGGGUACUUCAUCGACGCCACCACUAUCGUGGAGUGCCUGCAUUCCUUCUGCAAAACCUGCAUCGUGCGCUACCUGGAGACCAACAAAUACUGCCCCAUGUGUGACGUGCAGGUCCAUAAAACCCGGCCGCUGCUGAGCAUCAGGUCUGACAAAACACUUCAAGACAUUGUCUACAAAUUGGUCCCUGGGCUUUUUAAAGAUGAGAUGAAACGGCGGCGGGAUUUCUAUGCAGCGUACCCCCUGACGGAGGUCCCCAACGGCUCCAAUGAGGACCGCGGCGAGGUCUUGGAGCAGGAGAAGGGGGCUCUGAGUGAUGAUGAGAUUGUCAGCCUCUCCAUCGAAUUCUACGAAGGUGCCAGGGACCGGGACGAGAAGAAGGGCCCCCUGGAGAAUGGGGAUGGGGACAAAGAGAAAACAGGGGUGCGCUUCCUGCGAUGCCCAGCAGCCAUGACCGUCAUGCAUCUUGCCAAGUUUCUCCGCAACAAGAUGGAUGUGCCCAGCAAGUACAAGGUGGAGGUUCUGUACGAGGACGAGCCACUGAAGGAAUACUACACCCUCAUGGACAUCGCCUACAUCUACCCCUGGCGGCGGAACGGGCCUCUCCCCCUCAAGUACCGUGUCCAGCCAGCCUGCAAGCGGCUCACCCUAGCCACGGUGCCCACCCCCUCCGAGGGCACCAACACCAGCGGGGCGUCCGAGUGUGAGUCAGUCAGCGACAAGGCUCCCAGCCCUGCCACCCUGCCAGCCACCUCCUCCUCCCUGCCCAGCCCAGCCACCCCAUCCCAUGGCUCUCCCAGUUCCCAUGGGCCUCCAGCCACCCACCCUACCUCCCCCACUCCCCCUUCGACAGCCAGUGGGGCCACCACAGCUGCCAACGGGGGUAGCUUGAACUGCCUGCAGACACCAUCCUCCACCAGCAGGGGGCGCAAGAUGACUGUCAACGGCGCUCCCGUGCCCCCCUUAACUUGAGGCCAGGGACCCUCUCCCUUCUUCCAGCCAAGCCUCUCCACUCCUUCCACUUUUUCUGGGCCCUUUUUUCCACCUCUUCUACUUUCCCCAGCUCUUCCCACCUUGGGGGUGGGGGGCGGGUUUUAUAAAUAAAUAUAUAUAUAUAUGUACAUAGGAAAAACCAAAUAUACAUACUUAUUUUCUAUGGACCAACCAGAUUAAUUUAAAUGCCACAGGAAACAAACUUUAUGUGUGUGUGUAUGUGUGGAAAAUGGUGUUCAUUUUUUUUGGGGGGGGUCUUGUGUAAUUUGCUGUUUUUGGGGGUGCCUGGAGAUGAACUGGAUGGGCCACUGGAGUCUCAAUAAAGCUCUGCACCAUCCUCGCUGUUUCCCAAGGCAGGUGGUGUGUUGGGGGCCCCUUCAGACCCAAAGCUUUAGGCAUGAUUCCAACUGGCUGCAUAUAGGAGUCAGUUAGAAUCGUUUCUUUCUCUCCCCGUUUCUCUCCCCAUCUUGGCUGCUGUCCUGCCUCUGACCAGUGGCCGCCCCCCACGUUGUUGAAUGUCCAGAAAUUGCUAAGAACAGUGCCUUUUACAAAUGCAGUUUAUCCCUGGUUCUGAGGAGCAAGUGCAGGGUGGAGGUGGCACCUGCAUCACCUCCUCCUCUUGCAGUGGAAACUUUGUGCAAAGAAUAGAUAGUUCUGCCUCUUUUUUUUUUUUUCCUGUGUGUGUGGCCUUUGCAUCAUUUAUCUUGUGGAAAAGAAGAUUCAGGCCCUGAGAGGUCUCAGCUCUUGGAGGAGGGCUAAGGCUUUAGCAUUGUGAAGCGCUGCACCCCCACCAACCUUACCCUCACCGGGGAACCCUCACUAGCAGGACUGGUGGUGGAGUCUCACCUGGGGCCUAGAGUGGAAGUGGGGGUGGGUUAACCUCACACAAGCACAGAUCCCAGACUUUGCCAGAGGCAAACAGCCUUCCAAUUGCCCCUCCACCCCCAGCUGAGGCCCGGUCACCUGGUCAGGACAGAGCAACUGCAUCUAAAAGCACAAGAAGACAGAAACCUGUAAGCUCUGACCCCACCCCCACCCCUUGAGAGGUCAGCGGACCACCUCCUUAGGGACAGACCCUGGCAGGUCGCUGCCCACCGAGAUUUCCUCAAGUGUGCAUAGAUCUGAGAGGAGUCGGGAGUCGAGACUCGAGAUUCCAUCAUAGCGUAGGUGUGUGGGGUUGGGAGCCCCCUGAUGGGCUUGUCUGUGUUUGCACCUUGUCCUGUGUCUGAGGUCCUGUGACUGUACCCUCCUUUGCCCUGGGACAUCUGUAUCUCUUGGCUUUGUAAUAAAUGCUGCAUACUUUC